ACGCGCUGGCGGGACCCUCAGGGCUUUACCAGCAACUACCCCAGUGCCGGGGAGGGUUCUGCUGCUUCGAAAGCUGGUAAGGCCUGAGCUCUACCCUUCUCCAAAAGAAGAGCCAAGAGAAGGUCCUUUUCUACAAAUAUCAGAGCCAUGGCUCAGGAGUCAGUGAUGUUCAGUGAUGUGUCCGUAGACUUCUCUCAGGAGGAGUGGGAAUGCCUGAAUGAUGAUCAGAGAGAUUUAUACAGAGAUGUGAUGUUGGAGAAUUACAGCAACCUGGUUUCAAUGGCAGGGCAUUCUAUUUCUAAACCAAAUGUGAUCUCCUACUUGGAGCAAGGGAAGGAGCCCUGGUUGGCUGACAGAGAGCUAACAAGAGGCCAGUGGCCAGUCCUGGAAUCAAGAUGUGAGACCAAGAAAUUAUUUCUGAAGAAAGAAAUUUAUGAAAUAGAAUCAACCCAGUGGGAAAUAAUGGAAAAACUCACAAGACGUGAUUUUCAGUGCUCCAGUUUCAGAGAUGAUUGGGAAUGUAAUCGGCAGUUUAAGAAAGAACUCGGCUCUCAGGGGGGACAUUUCAAUCAAUUGGUAUUCACUCAUGAAGAUCUGCCCACUUUGAGUCACCAUCCAUCCUUCACAUUACAGCAAAUCAUUAACAGUAAAAAGAAAUUCUGUGCAUCUAAAGAAUAUAGGAAAACCUUUAGACAUGGCUCACAGUUUGCUACACAUGAGAUAAUUCAUACCAUUGAGAAGCCUUAUGAAUGUAAGGAAUGUGGAAAGUCCUUUAGACAUCCCUCAAGACUCACUCAUCAUCAGAAAAUUCAUACUGGCAAGAAACCCUUUGAAUGUAAGGAAUGUGGAAAAACCUUUAUUUGUGGCUCAGACCUUACUCGACAUCACAGAAUUCACACUGGUGAGAAACCCUAUGAAUGUAAGGAAUGUGGGAAAGCCUUUAGUAGUGGUUCAAACUUCACUCGACAUCAGAGAAUUCACACAGGUGAGAAGCCUUAUGAAUGCAAAGAAUGCGGGAAGGCCUUUAGUAGUGGCUCAAACUUUACUCAACAUCAGAGAAUUCAUACUGGGGAAAAACCCUAUGAAUGUAAGGAAUGUGGCAAUGCCUUUAGUCAGAGCUCACAACUUAUUAAACAUCAAAGAAUCCAUACAGGUGAGAAACCUUACGAAUGUAAGGAAUGUGAAAAGGCUUUUCGUUCUGGCUCAGACCUUACUAGACAUCAGAGAAUUCAUACUGGGGAGAAACCCUAUGAAUGUAAGAUAUGUGGGAAGGCUUAUUCUCAGAGUUCACAGCUUAUUAGUCAUCAUAGAAUUCAUACUAGUGAGAAACCCUAUGAAUAUAGGGAAUGUGGAAAGAACUUUAAUUAUGACCCACAACUUAUUCAGCAUCAAAAUUUGUACUGGUGAUGAAACAGAAUAUAUGAAAUGUGUAGGGAGGCUUUUAAUUAUGGCUCAAAACAGAAUUUAUCUUGUUAAUAAUUCCUCUAGAUAGAAUAAUGUAGAAACAUUUUAUUUGUGGACUACAGCUUAUUCAGCCUGGGAAAAAUAAUGUUGGAGAAAUACUCUAUGAAUAGAAUAUACUUUGGAAGCCCUUAACUAAACGCUUACUUCUCUUGACAUCAGAUAAUUCAGUCUAGCAAUAUGAUAGAUAAUUCAGUCUGUCAUACUGAAAAUGACAGCACUUUUAACACCUUUCUAACCUUCUUAACGUCAGAGAAUUUUUGUAGAAAUGUAGUCCUGUGAUUGUCAUUUUUUCCCCUAAUUUCUCUAAUUGUUACAUUCUUAGUAUUUUAAUCCAUAUUAAAUUUAUAUGGCUAUAAAUUUCAUCUGUUUACAUCCUGAUUUGUAUACUAUUUUAAAAAUACCUUUAGUACCUGGGAGAAGUGACCUCUUUAUUUUUGAAGAUGGCUUAUUCUUUUUGUUCUUUAUAACAUUAAGGCUUUCUUAUUGUAAAAAUGUUCAUGAACGACAUUUUACUCAAUAGAGAUUCUUCAUUAUCUUCAUGGUGUUUUGUUGUGUUACUGUAAUAUCACUUAUGAAAUCCUAUUGGUGGAUAUCGUAGUCUCCUCUAGAUAUUUUGCCAUAAUACAUGCCAAAAUACAAGUCCCUGCUGGACAUUCUCCCUAAGCACAUCUUUGUAUCAUAUCUUUUAAUUGCAGAAGUAAUGUGUGAAUAUAUUUUCCUUAUAAAAGAUGCAAACAUUACAAAAAGGCAAAUGUACCCUUUGACCAUAUCCCAAAGGAUAGUCUUUAUCAGUUCAUUAUUUAUUGCUGAUCAUUUUUCUGUUCAUAUAUACAUGCGUGUCUCAGUAAAAAUUAUAAAAUGGGGGAUAAUUAUAAUACCUACCUCAUAAUGCUUUGUGAGGAUUAAAUGAAUUAAGAUCGAUAAAGUGCUUAGAAUUGUGCCUGACAUGAUAAAUACAUACUCACUGAAUGUUAGUCAUCGUUAUUAUAUUCAUCAUCAUCAGUAUUAUUAUUUGUAGAAAGGCUUUUUAACUUCUGCAGAACUUAGUCACCAUUAGGCAGGGUGUUUGACUGAAGAAAGACCCUUUGAAGGUAACAAGUUAAGAAAAUUUCCCAUCAUCAUGUACUUACUAUUGAACAUGAAAUAAUCCUAGGUGUUGGGGGGGAAAGUACUGUGAAUAAUGUGUGUGAAGGACUUUAUUCCGACUAAUACUCUUUUUGUCGCAUUAUAUACCCAGUAAAAAAGAAAAGAGAACAUAAGCAAAAUAUUGGUGCACUAAUGAGGAAAAAAAGUAUGAAAAGAGAAACAGCAUCAUAUUUAAAAAAUGGACAGAGAUAGAAACAUAGUUACAGAUUUAAAAGGUUCUGUUGAAUAUUAUGCUUUUUUCUAAUAUGUUUGAAAAUUUAAACAAAAUGGUUUUUAAGGAAAAUAUACAUCAAUAUUGACUCCAAGAAAAUUAGGACUCUUCAAAGACUCUCAUAAACACAGAGAACAGGGAAAAAUUAGCAUGUGAUCAGUUAACUAUUACUAAUGAAGCACCAAAUCCAGUUUCUUUCUAAGGAAAACUUUAUCAAAUGUUCAAGGAACUAUUUCAGUUAUAUAGAAGUACACAUCUUGGCUCACGCCUGUAAUCCCAGCACUUUGGGAGGCUGAGAUGGAAGGAUCAUUUGAGGCCAGGAGCUUGAGACCAGCCUGGCCAACAUGUUGAAACCCCAUUUUUACUCAAAAAUACAAAACUUAGCCAGGCAUGGUGGCACAUGCCUGUAAUCCCAGCUACUGGGGAGGCUGAGGCAGGAGAAUCACUUGAAUGCAGGAGGUGGAGGUUGCAGUGAGCCAAGAUCACGCCAUGGCACUUCAGCCUGAGCGACAGAAUGAGACUAUUAAAAAAAAAAAAAAAAAGUCCACAGUGUAGCUUUGUUUGGGGUUAAGUUAGUGUUUUGAAAUGGGCCUUCCCUGUGCUCAAAACAUGCUCAGCAAGCAGCUCCCCACGCUGGACAGAUCGCAUAUGUGGAAGGAUGAAGUUUAUGUCUGUAGAACUGUUAUUUUAUGCCCCACUUCCUUUUUUCUUAGAUCCUGUGUAGACGGGUCUCUCUGAACAUUGUGUUACUUUACUUUACUGGCAUAAGGAAGUAAAAUAUUUCAUAAUAAAUUUGAGAAAAGUAGAGUGAGCAAAAAUACCUGCAAAUGAGAGAAUUACUAAAAAUGGACUGUUGUAAUGUUUUGCGUUAUCAAAAUGAAAACUGCCAAAUGAGAUUUUGUUUACUUUCUUUUCUUGUGUGCUUAUGUCUUUUAUAAAGUUCUUCAUCUAAAAUUAUAGAGAUAGUGCAUUUGCACCCAAAUUAAUGAAACAAUACCAUUAAAGAGAAAGAAAAGGGGCUGGGCACAGUGGCUUACGCCUGUAAUCCCAGUGCUUUGGGAGGCCAAGGCAGGGGGCAGCCUGGCCAAUAUAGUGAAACCCCAUCUCUACUAAAAAUACAAAAAUUAGCUGGGCGUGGUGGCAUGUGCCUGUAGUCCCAGCUGCUCGGAAGGCUGAGGCAGGAGAAUCGCUUGAACCCGGGAGGCGGAGGUUGCAGUGAGCUGAGAUCCUGACUGCACUCCAGCCUGCAUGACAGAGUCUCAAAAAAUCUGUCUCAAAAAAAAAAAAAAAAAAGAAAGAAAAAAUGAUUAUCUUUGCCCUUCUCCGUUCCUCAUUCCCUCCCCUCUGUCAAUUUUCUUCUGAAUAAUAUUUAAAGGUUGUGUAUAUUACCCAUAUAUUUCUUCAUGCUAAAACAUUAACACACAAUUAUUUUAUUAUGUUUUUACAGAAAAAUGGAUAACUAUACAUUUCCCUGAAAUUUGCUUUUUUACAUUCAACUGUACAUUUUGGAUUUUCCUUCAAUAGAUGAUGAUCUAACAGUCUUUCUGAUGGUUACAGUAUGUUCCACAGUGUUAUUUACCAAUGCCUUUUCAACCACUUUCCCAAUUGUGAUAUUAUGGAUUGUUUGCGCUUUUUUGCCAUCUAAAAGUAAUGCUGCAACAAACACUUUGUAUUCUUGUCUGUUUUAUUUCUAUAAAAUAAGCUUCCCAAGUCAUUUCCAGUGUUUUUGCUUUGUUUUGUUUUGAGACAGAGUUUCACUCUUGUUUCCCAGGCUGGAGUGCAAUGGCGCAAUCUUGGCUUACUGCAAUCUCCGCCUCCCGGGUUCAAGAGAUUCUCCUGCCUCAGCCUCCCAAGUAGCUGGGGUUACAGGUAUAUGCCACUACGCCUGGAAAAUUUUGUAUUUUUAGUAGAGACGGCAUUUUUCCAUGUUGGUCAGGCUGGUCUCGAACUCCUGACCUCAGGUGAUCCACCCUCCUCGGCCUCCCAAAGUGCUGGCAUUAUAGGCAUGAGCCACCGCACCCGGCGUCAUUUCCAGUGUUUUCUAUGUUUCCUAGGAAGGUUUUGCUUCUGGAAGAUUUCAGAGGGCAAGAGAAUAAAGGAGUGGAGUGCAGUUUUUCAUAUAUGUGAUUCUGUGAGUGUGUAUACACAGAGAUUUAAUAUUUUAAUACAUCAGGAAUUGAUUAUACGAUCUAAUGCAGGAUGUCAGACUUGUUUCUAUCCAGGAAUAAAACCAGUUAUGCCAGAAGUAACUAUUAUUCACCUUUCUCCUACUGAAUUAAAAUACUAUCAGUUGUAUAUUAAAUGCUCACAUCUAUUUCUGUUCUCCAUAUUCUAGCAAUCCUUGACACUUUUCAAUAGCUUUUAUUACUUGGAAAUAAAGAUGUAUGUAUAUAUUAUUAAUAUAUAGUUUAUUAUUUGGAAAUAAAGAUGUUUCUUCAUGAGAA